ACUAGCUGAGGUGGCAGUGGUUCCACCAACAUGGAGCUCUCGCAGAUGUCGGAGCUCAUGGGGCUGUCGGUGUUGCUUGGGCUGCUGGCCCUGAUGGCGACGGCGGCGGUAGCGCGGGGGUGGCUGCGCGCGGGGGAGGAGAGGAGCGGCCGGCCCGCCUGUAAGUGGGGCCGGGUCGGGUGGGGGCGGCCCGCGGUGUCCCGGCUCCCGGCCUCCUCGUGGUCCGACCUGCGGUUUGGGCCCGCGGCUGGUGGGGCCCGGCGACUCCAUGGGCCUCAGUUUCUCCUCUGGUAACGUGAGCUUCGCUUCCAGAGACGGGGACCCGCCUUGCCGGGUUAGGCGCACCUCCUGGGGCGGGACUGGCUCCAACCUGGGCCCCUUACUGCGGCUUUCUCUGUGGCCGAGGCCAGGCCGUCCCCGGGGUGGCCAGGAGAGCACCGUAAACUCUUCAGCCUGCUCCGUGGCCGCGAUCUCGGAAAAAGCACCAAUUCUGUGAUGUGCAGCAGCAUUUACUGGGCAUCUAUGACCCUGUGAUAGGCUUUGGGGUCUUUUUCUGUAAGGAGUCCAGUAAAGGAGAAGUACAUCUGUAUUAUGAACACCUAAAUAUGGCCCAGGAGCUUUUUUCCUGUUGGAAUUGGGGAGCAUCUGCAGUCAUUUACCACAUGCCAGCUUUGUGACUCAAUUAAGUAUCUUUUACAAAAGUGACUGGCUCCACUCCCCCGCACAGGACUCAACAGAUGUUGACUUCUCAUCCCCGAGUUCUUUCAGGCCAAAAAGCAAAUGGAUUUCCACCUGACAAAUCUUCGGGAUCCAAGAAGCAGAAACAAUAUCAGCGGAUUCGGAAGGAGAAGCCUCAACAACACAACUUCACCCACCGCCUCCUGGCUGCAGCUCUGAAGAGCCACAGCGGGAACAUAUCUUGCAUGGACUUUAGCAGCAAUGGCAAAUACCUGGCUACCUGUGCAGAUGAUCGCACCAUCCGCAUCUGGAGCACCAAGGACUUCCUGCAGCGAGAGCACCGCAGCAUGAGAGCCAACGUGGAGCUGGACCACGCCACCCUGGUGCGCUUCAGCCCUGACUGCAGAGCCUUCAUCGUCUGGCUGGCCAACGGGGACACCCUCCGUGUCUUCAAGAUGACCAAGCGGGAGGAUGGGGGCUACACCUUCACAGCCACCCCAGAGGACUUCCCUAAAAAGCACAAGGCGCCUGUCAUCGACAUUGGCAUUGCUAACACAGGGAAGUUUAUCAUGACUGCCUCCAGUGACACCACUGUCCUCAUCUGGAGCCUGAAGGGUCAAGUGCUGUCUACCAUCAACACCAACCAGAUGAACAACACACACGCUGCUGUAUCUCCCUGUGGCAGAUUUGUAGCCUCGUGUGGCUUCACCCCAGAUGUGAAGGUUUGGGAAGUCUGCUUUGGAAAGAAGGGGGAGUUCCAGGAGGUGGUGCGAGCCUUCGAACUAAAGGGCCACUCCGCGGCUGUGCACUCGUUUGCUUUCUCCAACGACUCACGGAGGAUGGCUUCUGUCUCCAAGGAUGGUACAUGGAAACUGUGGGACACAGAUGUGGAAUACAAGAAGAAGCAGGACCCCUACUUGCUGAAGACAGGCCGCUUUGAAGAGGCGGCGGGUGCCGCGCCGUGCCGCCUGGCCCUCUCCCCCAACGCCCAGGUCUUGGCCUUGGCCAGUGGCAGUAGUAUUCAUCUCUACAAUACCCGGCGGGGCGAGAAGGAGGAGUGCUUUGAGCGGGUCCAUGGCGAGUGUAUCGCCAACUUGUCCUUUGACAUCACUGGCCGCUUUCUGGCCUCCUGUGGGGACCGGGCGGUGCGGCUGUUUCACAACACUCCUGGCCACCGAGCCAUGGUGGAGGAGAUGCAGGGCCACCUGAAGCGGGCCUCCAACGAGAGCACCCGCCAGAGGCUGCAGCAGCAGCUGACCCAGGCCCAAGAGACCCUGAAGAGCCUGGGUGCCCUGAAGAAGUGACUCUGGGAGGGCCCGGCGCAGAGGAUUGAGGAGGAGGGAUCUGGCCUCCUCAUGGCACUGCUGCCAUCUUUCCUCCCAGGUGGAAGCCUUUCAGAAGGAGUCUCCUGGUUUUCUUACUGGUGGCCCUGCUUCUUCCCAUUGAAACUACUCUUGUCUACUUAGGUCUCUCUCUUCUUGCUGGCUGUGACUCCUCCCUGACUAGUGGCCAAGGUGCUUUUCUUCCUCCCAGGCCCAGUGGGUGGAAUCUGUCCCCACCUGGCACUGAGGAGAAUGGUAGAGAGGAGAGGAGAGAGAGAGAGAAUGUGAUUUUUGGCCUUGUGGCAGCACAUCCUCACACCCAAAGAAGUUUGUAAAUGUUCCAGAACAACCUAGAGAACACCUGAGUACUAAGCAGCAGUUUUGCAAGGAUGGGAGACUGGGAUAGCUUCCCAUCACAGAACUGUGUUCCAUCAAAAAGACACUAAGGGAUUUCCUUCUGGGCCUCAGUUCUAUUUGUAAGAUGGAGAAUAAUCCUCUCUGUGAACUCCUUGCAAAGAUGAUAUGAGGCUAAGAGAAUAUCAAGUCCCCAGGUCUGGAAGAAAAGUAGAAAAGAGUAGUACUAUUGUCCAAUGUCAUGAAAGUGGUAAAAGUGGGAACCAGUGUGCUUUGAAACCAAAUUAGAAACACAUUCCUUGGGAAGGCAAAGUUUUCUGGGACUUGAUCAUACAUUUUAUAUGGUUGGGACUUCUCUCUUCGGGAGAUGAUAUCUUGUUUAAGGAGACCUCUUUUCAGUUCAUCAAGUUCAUCAGAUAUUUGAGUGCCCACUCUGUGCCCAAAUAAAUAUGAGCUGGGGAUUAAAUACGAAUAAGACAUGGUUUCUGCCAUCAAAGAUGGCUGGUGGGAGAGAGAGAUACACCCUUAUUAAGUGCUUUGUGUUAGUUUAUUCAUAGCUAUUGUUAUAUAUGUCAAGGCAAGAGAGGACCAGAGCAGGACAGAGGCAAUGGGUAUUGAAGUUGAAGGGGUACAUUUGAUAAGAGAGUCGGUAUUGAGAAGUUUAAAUUUGUGAAUUUGAAGGCUGCGUGGGUGUGGCAGGUAAGGGAAAUGAGGUAUCUGGGAAGGCUUGAGUGUAGGCAAAUUUAUUCAUCCCAAGUCAAACUCUUGAUCUCUCUCACGAAAACUAUGACCCCCCCUGGUUGCCCCUGACCUCUCAAUGUUGGAACAAGCCACAACCGUGGAGUUAUCCUUGAUGACUCCCCAUUCAUUAUCCCUUCUGUCCCACCACCACAGCUGUCAUCUGUUCACCAGAACGUUCUUUUGGUUACACUCCAUGUGACAUCCUGAGGCUGUUGCUUCUCUCCAGCUUUUCUGUUACCAUCCUGGUCCUGGCUACUGUCACCUAGUGGGCCACUAUAAUAUGGCUUCCUAAUGGAUCUUCCUGCUUCCUCUGUUGCCUCAUUACUUUUCUAUAUAGCAGAAUGAUCUUUUGAAAAUGUGAACCAGAUCACAUUAUUCCCUAGUUAAAACCCCCCAAGGCUUCCCAUCACACUUGGAAUAAAAUCCAAAAGAAUUUUUCUAAACCAAAAAUAGUAAAAACAAUUUUUUUUUUCUGACAAUCUCUUGUCACCCAGGCUGGAGUACAAUGGCGCAAUCUCGGCUCACUGCAACCGCCGCCUCCUAGGUUCAAGCGAUUCUCCUGCCUCAGCCUCCAGAGUAGCUGGGAUUACAGGCAUGUGCCACCACGCCUGGCUAAUUUUUGUAUUUUUAGUAGAGACAGGGUUUCACGAUGUUGGCCAGGCUGCUCUCGAACUCCUGACCUCAAAUGAUCCACCACCCCCCUUGGCCUCCCCAAGUGCUGGGAUUACAGGUGUGAGCCAUCGUGCCUAGCUAAAAACACUUAAUCCAAAAUUCUUACCAUGGCCUGCAAGGUCCUGUGUAACCUGGCUUCGUCCCCCCUCUAAAUGCUAUGAAUGUCAGAUGGGCACCGUAAAUGUGUGAAGGGUCAGUUACCUGGGUGUAAGGCAGUAGAAGGUGGGGACAGAAGUGAGCUGGAGGGCGGGCUUGUGUCCUGCCUGCAGGAUGGGGGGUGGCUGCUACUUAUUCAGGAAUCCAGCAGAAAUUGCUUCACAGAAGCUAGAAGUGAGCAACUUAAAUAACUAAACACUAUCUGGACCAAACAAAACACUAAGGUCGGCCCGAUGCAGUCCACUACUCUCUUAUUGGCAGCUUCUGGCUCACUGUUGAACCCACUGGAAUGAGAGCACCACCGGGCAGACUCCUGGACCAUCCCACUGUCAGCUCUGUGGUCCAGGCACAGUACCUGGGACAGUGUAAGCACUCAAUGUGAAACUCAAGCCAGGGGCAAGCCACAGACCUCCCAGUAUCUUCUCCGCGCAUCUUCCCACUCCCAGUCUCCAUUGUGGUUUUGUAUGUUCCUAACCACAGACUUUUGGCAAUGCUGUGCACACAAGGCCUGAGGAGUAUUUCCUUGGCAAUUGUCAGAAGAAUGAGACUAAAACACUUCCUUUGCGCACCUGUUCUUAGAAGCAGCUCUGGCAUUACUCCCGUUGUGUAUCCAGGACAGGAAGUGGCAGUAGAAUGUUGAGUUACUGAAGUCAGAUGUCUUCAGUUCCAGUUCCAGCUGGAGAGCAGAUAGUAGGUCCGUUGACCUCUCUGAGCUUGUUUCCUCAGCUGCAAAAUAAGAAUGAAUCCUGUGCUACCCACCUUGCCAUGUUGUGUUUCAGUGAGACGAGAAAACACUACCAAAAAGUCAUUCCACAGACUUCUGAGGACAGAAAGUGCCCUCACUCAAGCUUCUCUUGUAACCACAGAGAAGGUGUCUGGAUAUUAACAUAGAGCAGAGGCCACCAAGGUUUUUCUUUUUUUUAAUCAAAAAUCCUGCAUGUGAAGGCAGUAAUUGUAUCUUAAUAUUAUAAUUUCAACAUCUGUGGGUGUGAAAUUUUUCAAAAAAAAAAUUUGGGGAAAUAUUUUAAA